GGUGACAACGGCAACAUGGCCCUGAACGGAGCUGGUGAGGACCUGGGCGGCAGGGGUUUGUGGCUGUGAGGUACGGGAGGCAGCCCACUCCGGCAAGACCCCCAGUCCCUAUGCCUCUCUUCCCCAGAAGUCGACGACUUCUCCUGGGAGCCCCCGACUGAGGCGGAGACGAAGGUGCUGCAGGCGCGACGGGAGCGGCAAGAUCGCAUCUCCCGGCUCAUGGGCGACUAUCUGCUGCGCGGUUACCGCAUGCUGGGCGAGACGUGUGCGGACUGCGGGACGAUCCUCCUCCAAGACAAACAGCGGAAAAUCUACUGCGUGGCUUGUCAGGAACUCGACUCAGACGUGGAUAAAGAUAAUCCCGCUCUGAAUGCCCAGGCUGCCCUCUCCCAAGCUCGGGAGCACCAGCUGGCCUCAGCCUCAGAGCUCCCCCUGGGCUCUCGACCUGCGCCCCAGCCCCCAGUACCUCGUCCGGAGCACUGUGAGGGAGCUGCAGCAGGACUCAAGGCAGCCCAGGGGCCACCUGCUCCUGCUGUGCCUCCAAAUACAGAUGUCAUGGCCUGCACACAGACAGCCCUCUUGCAGAAGCUGACCUGGGCCUCUGCUGAACUGGGCUCUAGCACCUCCCUGGAGACUAGCAUCCAGCUGUGUGGCCUUAUCCGCGCAUGUGCGGAGGCCCUGCGCAGCCUGCAGCAGCUACAGCACUAAGAGAAGCCCCUGAGAAAAACCCUCUAGAAAAACAGCUGUUCCUCUGUGUGGUUUGUUUUUUUCCUGGUUCCAAGUGUGCAUGCCAGCCCCAGCUCCACUCACCUUUUUCCAGCUUUUGGCCUCUUCACCUCUCCACUCUGCUCUCCUUGACGCC